ACUCUUUCCCCAGCCCAGCUCACUCUCCAAUCUGCGGUCACCACCCGAGACCUUCCUGGGGGUCGCGCCUAAAAGGAGCGCAGACUCCCGCCGGGAUGGCCCAGAAGCUGGGGUGCGCGCACCCUGGCCGUCCCUGCCUGGGAGCCGAUCUCCCUCUCCUCACCCAGACACGUUCCAGCGGAGGCCUCCUCCCAGAAGGGCUCUGGAGGCCUCGCAGGAGUGGGGAUCCCGCGGUUCUGAGUUGGCACAAGGAAGAGAGUGGCACCAGGGGCCUGGAGUGGAUGGCAGGGUCCGGGAGUGGGGCCGCUGCUUUGCAAGAGGGGCCCCCACGCUGGGCAUCUUUGGGUGCCAGCGUGGGUGGAGGAGGGUCUUUUGCUGAGAAUGGCUUUCUCCUGACCGCAGUCUUUGCUGCUGGGAAGUGACUGAUGGGCUUUCGCCUUUUGUUUCCAUUUCCUGUCGGUGUUAGAAUUGGGGAGGGGGUGGAAAUCCCUUCUUGGCCUGGAAGGACUGGAGUGGGUGUCCAUGGCCGCGGCCUCCCCGUGGCCACGCCCCUGGGCAUAGACUGCAAGCCCCUCCCCGUGCCCCCCAGGCUGUCACCCCCUUCUCGUGGAAGACUCGGCUGAUGUCCCAGUGGACCGAGUGUUUCUCAAGUUGAGGCAGGGAGGGCAAACUUUUUAAAUGGCCCCUGGAGCCAGUGUGUGGGACCAGAGACAUCUGUUUCCCAUCUGGACGGCUGAGGAUCCCAGUGCGGAUGAUUAUUUGGAGGGGGAAGGACGGAGGCUGAACUGAACUCUCAGCUGGGAGAUGAGUGGGGCAGUCACAUCCCACCUUCCCCAAGCCGGGCUGUUCUGCACAGCCUGCUUGGGACGCUGGUGGGAGUCACUGUGGCCUUCGGCACUGCCCUGGCAGUGGGGGCAGCUAGGCCAUUUGGGAGGGGCUCGCCUUCCCCAGGCCCGGCCCUGGGACCUCAGCCGUUGCUUAGUGGUGGCCUGCUUCAGCCCAGGCAUGUGGGAGAGGCACCAGACACAGGAUGUCCCUCUGCCAGCCCCUGAAGCCCCGUCCCCUGACGAGCUGGCUGGAGGCGUGAUCCUGGGUGUGGCCCUGUGGCUCCGCCAUGACCCGCAGACCACCAACCUCCUGUAUCUGGAGCUGGGAGACAAGCCCGCGCCCAACACCUUCUAUGUAGGCAUCUACAUCCUCAUCGCUGUGGGCGCUGUCAUGAUGUUCGUUGGCUUCCUGGGCUGCUACGGGGCCAUCCAGGAAUCCCAGUGCCUGCUGGGGACGUUCUUCACCUGCCUGGUCAUCCUGUUUGCCUGUGAGGUGGCCGCCGGCAUCUGGGGCUUUGUCAACAAGGACCAGAUCGCCAAGGAUGUGAAGCAGUUCUAUGACCAGGCCCUACAGCAGGCCGUGGUGGAUGAUGACGCCAACAACGCCAAGGCUGUGGUGAAGACCUUCCACGAGACGCUUGACUGCUGUGGCUCCAGCACACUGACUGCUUUGACCACCUCAGUGCUCAAGAACAAUUUGUGUCCCUCGGGCAGCAACAUCAUCAGCAACCUCUUCAAGGAGGACUGCCACCAGAAGAUCGAUGACCUCUUCUCCGGGAAGCUGUACCUCAUCGGCAUUGCUGCCAUCGUGGUCGCUGUGAUCAUGAUCUUCGAGAUGAUCCUGAGCAUGGUGCUGUGCUGUGGCAUCCGGAACAGCUCCGUGUACUGAGGCCCCGCAGCUCUGGCCACAGGGACCUCUGCAGUGCCCCCUAAGUGACCCGGACACUUCCGAGGGGGCCAUCACCGCCUGUGUAUAUAACGUUUCCGGUAUUACUCUGCUACACGUAGCCUUUUUACUUUUGGGGUUUUGUUUUUGUUCUGAACUUUCCUGUUACCUUUUCAGGGCUGACGUCACAUGUAGGUGGCGUGUAUGAGUGGAGACGGGCCUGGGUCUUGGGGACUGGAGGGCAGGGGUCCUUCUGCCCUGGGGUCCCAGGGUGCUCUGCCUGCUCAGCCAGGCCUCUCCUGGGAGCCACUCGCCCAGAGACUCAGCUUGGCCAACUUGGGGGGCUGUGUCCACCCAGCCCGCCCGUCCUGUGGGCUGCACAGCUCACCUUGUUCCCUCCUGCCCCGGUUCGAGAGCCGAGUCUGUGGGCACUCUCUGCCUUCAUGCACCUGUCCUUUCUAACACGUCGCCUUCAACUGUAAUCACAACAUCCUGACUCCGUCAUUUAAUAAAGAAGGAACAUCAGGCAUGCUA